AUUCCCCAGACCUUCUGCAGAUUCUGUGGUUAUACUCACUCCUCAUCCCAAAGAAUGAAAUUUACCACUCUCCUCUUCUUGGCAGCUGUAGCAGGGGCCCUGGUCUAUGCUGAAGAUGCCUCCUCUGACUCGACGGGUGCUGAUCCUGCCCAGGAAGCUGGGACCUCUAAGCCUAAUGAAGAGAUCUCAGGUCCAGCAGAACCAGCUUCACCCCCAGAGACAACCACAACAGCCCAGGAGACUUCGGCGGCAGCAGUUCAGGGGACAGCCAAGGUCACCUCAAGCAGGCAGGAACUAAACCCCCUGAAAUCCAUAGUGGAGAAAAGUAUCUUACUAACAGAACAAGCCCUUGCAAAAGCAGGAAAAGGAAUGCACGGAGGCGUGCCAGGUGGAAAACAAUUCAUCGAAAAUGGAAGUGAAUUUGCACAAAAAUUACUGAAGAAAUUCAGUCUAUUAAAACCAUGGGCAUGAGAAGCUGAAAAGAAUGGGAUCAUUGGACUUAAAGCCUUAAAUACCCUUGUAGCCCAGAGCUAUUAAAACGAAAGCAUCCAA